GACCGGCACGCGGCGAGCCUCGAGACUGCGCGAGGGCGGCCCCGGGGGCGAGCGGCUGUGCGCGGGGCCAAGGGCGGGGGCAGCAGGUGAGUGCGCGGCCGGGCGGGAGUUCUGGGCGGCCGGGCGGGAGUUCUGGGCACUCGCGCGCGGCAGAGGAGCCCCGCGAGCCCUGCCCUCGGUACUGGGGGCCCCCGGAGCGUGGCGCUUCCGAGCCACCCGCCUCCCCGGGCCCCAUCCCUCGGCGCGCGGGAAAGUUGGGGCAGGGGUGAGGACCGCGCGGUCGGGGCGCCCCAGCCAGCCGGGCCGCUGGCGUCGGACUGUCUGUUCCAUUUGUCCCUUGUCACCCUUGUCUCCUCCCCCUAGGCCGGAGUCCUGAAAGUCGAGCGAGCUCCGGGUUUUGAAAAUGUUGGAGGGAAAAGCUCCUCGGAGAUGAGCGUGACCCCCUGGCUCGUGGUGGCCGCCUGUUCUCACUAACGCCAUGGCGGGGACCGGAGUGAGAAACCGGUGUCUGUCACUGACUGCAAAGUGAGCGAGAAGCAGGCUGCGGGCCGUCCCAGCACGACGUGGAGCCCCGCGGAGACCUCGAGAUGCCCCGCGGGGAAGCUCCUGGCCCCGGGAGACGGGGGGCUAAGGACGAGGCCCUGGGCGAAGAAUCGGGGGAGCGGUGGAGCCCCGAGUUCCAUCUGCAGAGGAAAUUGGCGGACAGCAGCCACAGUGAACAGCAAGAUCGAAACAGAGUUUCUGAAGAACUUAUCAUGGUUGUCCAAGAAAUGAAAAAAUACUUCCCCUCGGAGAGACGCAAUAAACCAAGCACUCUAGAUGCCCUCAACUAUGCUCUCCGCUGUGUCCACAGCGUUCAAGCAAACAGUGAGUUUUUCCAGAUUCUCAGUCAGAAUGGAGCACCUCAGGCAGAUGUGAGCAUGUACAGUCUUGAGGAGCUGGCCACUAUCGCUUCAGAACACACUUCCAAAAACACAGAUACCUUUGUGGCAGUAUUUUCAUUUCUGUCUGGAAGGUUAGUGCACAUUUCUGAACAGGCUGCUUUGAUCCUGAAUCGUAAGAAAGAUGUCCUGGCGUCUUCUCACUUUGUUGACCUGCUUGCACCUCAAGACAUGAGGGUAUUCUACGCGCACACUGCCAGAGCUCAGCUUCCUUUCUGGAACAACUGGACCCAAAGAGCAGCUGCACGGUAUGAAUGUGCUCCGGUGAAACCUUUUUUCUGCAGGAUCCGUGGAGGUGAAGACAGAAAGCAAGAGAAGUGUCACUCCCCAUUCCGGAUCAUCCCCUAUCUGAUUCAUGUACAUCACCCUGCCCAGCCAGAAUUGGAAUCGGAACCUUGCUGUCUCACUGUGGUUGAAAAGAUUCACUCUGGUUAUGAAGCUCCUCGGAUCCCAGUGAAUAAAAGAAUCUUCACCACCACACACACCCCAGGGUGUGUUUUUCUUGAAGUAGAUGAAAAAGCAGUGCCUUUGCUGGGUUACCUACCUCAGGACCUGAUUGGAACAUCGAUCCUAAGCUACCUGCACCCUGAAGAUCGUUCUCUGAUGGUUGCCAUACACCAAAAAGUUUUGAAGUAUGCAGGGCAUCCUCCCUUUGAACAUUCUCCCAUUCGAUUUUGUACUCAAAACGGAGACUACAUCAUACUGGAUUCCAGUUGGUCCAGCUUUGUGAAUCCCUGGAGCCGGAAGAUUUCUUUCAUCAUUGGUCGGCAUAAAGUUCGAACGAGCCCACUAAAUGAGGAUGUUUUUGCUACCAAAAUUAAAAAGAUGAACGAUAAUGACAAAGACAUAACAGAAUUACAAGAACAAAUUUACAAACUUCUCUUACAGCCAGUUCACGUGAGCGUGUCCAGCGGCUACGGGAGCCUGGGGAGCAGCGGGUCGCAGGAGCAGCUUGUCAGCAUCGCCUCCUCCAGUGAGGCCAGUGGGCACCGUGUGGAGGAGACGAAGGCGGAGCAGAUGACCUUGCAGCAGGUCUAUGCCAGUGUGAACAAAAUUAAAAAUCUGGGUCAGCAGCUCUACAUUGAGUCAAUGACCAAAUCAUCAUUCAAGCCAGUGACGGGGACACGCACAGAACCGAAUGGUGGUGGUGAGUCAGCGAAUGGUGGUGGUGAAUGUAAGACCUUUACUUCCUUCCACCAAACACUGAAAAACAAUAGUGUGUACACUGAGCCCUGUGAGGAUUUGAGGAACGAUGAGCACAGCCCAUCCUAUCAACAGAUCAACUGUAUCGACAGUGUCAUCAGAUACCUGAAGAGCUACAACAUUCCAGCUUUGAAAAGAAAGUGUAUCUCCUGUACAAAUACAACUUCUUCCUCCUCAGAAGAAGACAAACAGAACCACAAGGCAGAUGAUGUCCAAGCCUUACAAGCUGGUUUGCAAAUCCCAGCCAUACCUAAAUCAGAAAUGCCAACAAAUGGACGGUCCAUAGACACAGGAGGAGGAGCUCCACAGAUCCUGUCCACGGCGAUGCUGAGCUUGGGGUCGGGCAUAAGCCAAUGCGGUUACAGCAGCACCAUUGUCCAUGUCCCACCCCCAGAGACAGCCAGGGAUGCUACCCUCUUCUGUGAGCCCUGGACCCUGAACAUGCAGCCAGCCCCUUUGACCUCGGAAGAAUUUAAACACGUGGGGCUCACAGCGGCUGUUCUGUCAGCGCACACCCAGAAGGAAGAGCAGAAUUAUGUUGAUAAAUUCCGAGAAAAGAUCCUGUCAUCACCCUACAGCUCCUAUCUUCAGCAAGAAAGCAGGAGCAAAGCUAAAUAUUCAUAUUUUCAAGGAGAUUCUACUUCCAAGCAGACGCGGUCGGCCGGCUGCAGGAAAGGGAAGCACAAGCGGAAGAAGCUGCCGGAGCCGCCAGACAGCAGCAGCUCGAACACCGGCUCUGGUCCCCGCAGGGGAGCGCAUCAGAACGCACAGCCCUGCUGCCCCUCCGCGGCCUCCUCUCCGCACACCUCGAGCCCGACCUUCCCACCUGCCGCCAUGGUGCCCAGCCAGGCCCCUUACCUCGUCCCAGCUUUUCCCCUCCCAGCCGCGACCUCACCCGGAAGAGAAUACGCAGCCCCCGGAACUGCACCGGAAGGCCUGCAUGGGCUGCCCUUGUCCGAGGGCUUGCAGCCUUACCCAGCUUUCCCUUUUCCUUACUUGGAUACUUUUAUGACCGUUUUCCUGCCUGACCCCCCUGUCUGUCCUCUGUUGUCGCCAUCGUUUUUGCCAUGUCCAUUCCUGGGGGCGACAGCCUCUUCUGCGAUAUCACCCUCAAUGUCGUCAGCAAUGAGUCCAACUCUGGACCCACCCCCUUCAGUCACCAGCCAAAGGAGAGAGGAGGAAAAGUGGGAGGCACAAAGCGAGGGGCACCCGUUCAUUACUUCGAGAAGCAGCUCACCCUUGCAGUUAAACUUACUUCAGGAAGAGAUGCCCAGACCCUCUGAAUCUCCAGAUCAGAUGAGAAGGAACACGUGCCCACAAACUGAGUAUUGUGUUACAGGCAACAAUGGCAGUGAGAGCAGUCCUGCUACUACCGGUGCACUGUCCACGGGGUCACCUCCCAGGGAGAAUCCAUCCCAUCCUACUGCCAGCGCUCUGUCCACAGGAUCGCCUCCCAUGAAGAAUCCAUCCCAUCCUACUGCCAGCGCUCUGUCCACAGGAUCGCCUCCCAUGAAGAAUCCAUCCCAUCCUACUGCCAGCACACUGUCCAUGGGAUUGCCUCCCAGCAGGACUCCAUCCCAUCCUACUGCCACUGUUCUGUCCACGGGGUCACCUCCCAGCGAAUCCCCAUCCAGAACUGGUUCAGCAGCAUCAGGAAGCAGCGACAGCAGUAUAUACCUUACUAGUAGUGUUUAUUCUUCUAAAAUCUCCCAAAAUGGGCAGCAAUCUCAGGACGUACAGAAAAAAGAAACAUUUCCUAAUGUCGCCGAAGAGCCCAUCUGGAGAAUGAUACGGCAGACACCUGAGCGCAUUCUCAUGACAUACCAGGUACCUGAGAGGGUUAAAGAAGUUGUACUAAAAGAAGACCUGGAAAAGCUAGAAAGUAUGAGGCAGCAGCAGCCCCAGUUUUCUCAUGGGCAAAAGGAGGAGCUGGCUAAGGUGUAUAAUUGGAUUCAAAGCCAGACUGUCACUCAAGAAAUCGACAUUCAAGUGACAUUGACAUCAAGUAACUCGCCUGCUUUGUUCUUUUUUGGAGGCCUGUGUCACUUGUGAAAAUGAAGAUUCAGCUGAUGGUGCGGCCACAUCCUGUGGUCAGGUUCUGGUAGAAGACAGCUGUUGAGUGACUGUGAGGAUGAACCUUCAUACCCUUUCCAAGACGUGUUACACAGACAGACCUUUUUAAGUCCUGGACUUUUAAAUGACCAUGAAGUUAUCAUUGAAUGUUAAGAUUUUUUCUUCUUGAUUUUUUAAUACACGUAAUCUUUUUGAAGCAGACAUUGUAUACAGAAUCUUACUUCUCUUUGUUCCUGAUAUAUUAAAAUGGCCAGUUAGGCUCUUUUUGUAGUUGAAUUGUCUUCUAAAGAGAUUGGAUGGCCUCUAAAGAGGUAUGUGUAUCUUUAUUUCAGAUGUCACCCAGAGUAAAUUAUAAUUAGAAGUAUAGCUAGAAUGAGCCCCAAACCUUAGCCUCAUUUAUUUUGUUCUGUUACAUAAGUCAUUUUCCCCUUAGAGUGCUUGAAGAAAUGCCACCUACAGGUUGUGUACUUUUCAUAAUGGUUUCCAUGAAUGUAGUACGUUCAUACAGGCUUCAUUCAACCUGGCGUUCCCCUCCAUAAUUAAGAUGAAACAUUCCGGUUUUCUCACAACACAUUAGCACAUACUGUCCAUUAGCAUAUCUGGGAUAACCAGGUUUUGGGGGUUGAGUUUUGGCCUUCAUCCUUGUAGAUCCCUUUCCUAUUGAUUUCCCACCUUCCAGUGAAAUUCUGAAAGUCUUAUCUUAAAAAUCGAUCCGCUUACCAUGGGCCUAUUCUUGUAAGUUUCAGUUAGCAUUUGCAUGUGUAAUAUUAAAAUGAAAGAGCUUCUUACCCAGUGCUGUUGCCCUUUUGAGUAUUUUUGUUUUUAAAAUAAUGAUUGUAAAAUGUUUUACAAGUAAUGUAAAAGCUAGUAUCAUUCUUACAUACUUCUGUGUUUAAAUUUUCAUUCUUACCAAAACAGUUAACUCUUUCUUUCCAAUCAAUUUAUACAAAAGAGGUCGCUCCAGCCCUACCACAGGUCUGACUGGCACUGCCUUUUGUUUGCCCUUGAACAGGGCAGUGUUGUGGGGACUGCAAAAGAGAAAACGUCCAGGCGAGCCCAGUUGUCCUCGCCCACAGGGUCCUGCAGGCUCCAUCAGUCACCGCUUUCUAUGGCGUUUGUAGUUGUGUCUUUUAAGAAGUGAGUGUGAUUGUUUACUUGAUAAAUCAGCUCACUCUCUGGUGCUUUUUAGAGAAGUCCCUGAUUCCUUCUUAAACUUGGAAUGAUAGAUGAAAUUCACACCCCUGCAGAUCAGAAAAAACAAAUAGAAGAAAAUGAGGGUUACAGUAACCUGUUGUCUUUAUAUAACUUGCAACAAACUAAUUUAUUUUUUUUUCCUUUUUUUGUUUUUGGUUUUUUAUGGUUUUUUAAGGAAAAUACUUUUCUCCUUUGAAGUUUUACAGCUUUUUGUAAAUGCGUCCUGAUAAUGAUUAGGAAAAUCGACCUUUUCAUCCAUGAUGACCAUCCUCAUAGCUCAGAUCUCCUUUCAAAGUAGUGGCUUUCUGGAUGGUAAUUCCAUCUUAAGGUGUCAGAACUAUUUUCAAAUGCUGCCUUUGACAGUUCUUGGAAUUUUCUGAUAUUAAGCAGUUCCAUGCAAAUAUUCGUGUUUUAUAAAUAGCUCUCAUAGUCUGCUCCAUCUUGAUAGUUAAGUGAUUUCUGAAGCGUUUGUGUGUGUGUUGAUCAGGUUGUGUGAUAUUUUUGCUUGAUAGAGAAUCAAAUUUGAAACAAUUAACCAGCCAGUAGAUUGUCUGUCAGUGACCUUCUGUAGUAAUAAAGUUUUUGCCACUGUAAAUAAAAACAGUAUCCGUAGCUAUCAGGAUCAUUGCGCACUCAUAUAUGCUAAGCCUUCUGUUCUCUAAUAGAAGCCUUUCUUUUCCAUUGUUUCUGGAUAUUUGUAUUAUCCAAAUGUGCUUAUUUCUUUGCCUUAGCACACGUUUUAUGGAGUACUUGUUAUACUAGGUUUGAUUUGAAACUGGUGCUUGUCGCAGAACUGUCAGAGCAUGAGGAGCGCUCCUCCUGUGGGUGGACGCAUUCACGCACUCCCAGGUUGCACCUGCUGCUGGCGGUGAGCAGGGGGUUCAGCAGCUUGACCGAUGCCCCCCGAGGGGGCUCUCCCCAGCUUAAACUUUGUUGUUUAAAUUUGUUAACUUUUUAUAUUAAUGACUAUUGAAAGUGGUAAUAAAAAUUUAUAUUAUAGGCUUCAAUGUUUUCAUGAAUGUUACCCAAAAAGCUGUGUUUUCUUUGGUCAGAGGUCAAAAUUUAUGAAAAACAAAAUGCUGUAUGAAUGGAAAUCAUUUUGCAAUUGAGUGACACUUCAUUGUAAUUCACAGUGUAAAUUUAAUCCAAACUGAAAUUUUGUUUCAACUGAAUUUGUAAUUAACUCUGAAUUUGUUUUUAAUCAUUAGUAAUAUUUCAGUUGGGUAUCUUUUUAAGUAAAAACAACAAAUAAACUCUGUACAUGUAAAACGUGA